AGAUCGGCUUCCGGUUCCGGUGGGCUCUGAACCCUGAAAGGUGGGCGCGGGCAGGUGGGGUGUGGGGGGGCGCCGGGGCAGAAGGGGAGGGGCAGGCUCGCGAUGCCUCUACACAAGUAUCCCGUGUGGCUCUGGAAGCGGCUGCAGCUGCGGGAGGGCAUCUGUUCCCGCCUGCCCGGCCACUACCUGCGCUCCCUGGAGGAGGAGCGGACGCCCACUCCCGUGCACUAUAGGCCUCAUGGGGCCAAGUUCAAGAUCAACCCCAAGAACGGGCAGCGGGAGCGUGUGGAGGACGUGCCCAUUCCCAUCUACUUUCCCCCCGAAUCCCAGCGGGGGUUGUGGGGCGGCGAGGGCUGGAUCCUGGGCCAAAUAUAUGCCAACAACGACAAGCUCUCCAAGAGGCUGAAGAAAGUGUGGAAGCCACAGCUGUUUGAGCGAGAGUUCUACAGUGAGAUCCUGGACAAGAAGUUCACAGUGACUGUGACCAUGCGGACCCUGGACCUCAUCGAUGAGGCUUAUGGGCUCGACUUUUACAUCCUCAAGACCCCGAAGGAGGACCUGUGCUCCAAGUUUGGGAUGGACCUGAAGCGAGGGAUGCUGCUGCGGCUUGCCCGGCAGGACCCCCAGCUGCACCCCGAGGACCCCGAGCGGCGGGCAGCCAUCUACGACAAGUACAAGGAAUUUGCCAUCCCAGAGGAGGAGGCAGAGUGGGUGGGCCUCACGCUGGAGGAGGCCAUUGAGAAGCAGAGACUUUUGGAGGAGAAGGACCCUGUACCCCUGUUCAAGAUCUAUGUGGCGGAGCUGAUCCAGCAGCUGCAGCAGCAGGCACUGUCAGAGCCGGCGGUGGUGCAGAAGAGAGCCAGUGGCCAGUGACCACACAGCUCCUCCAUGCCUGACCAACAGGCCCAGCUUUCCCUGCCAGGCCCUUUGCACUGAGGACACAGAUCCCGGGGAGCUGUGAGGGCCACCGGUGGGCAGUGGGUGGAUCCUGGUUUCGUGUGCUGCCCAUGCACCUUCCAGCCCGGGGCCAGCUUGGCAGGGAUCCCCAGGAGGCCUGGGCCGCCCAGAGGCUCCUCUCAGGCUGGGCCCCGACGUUUGCGGCAGUGUUCCUUGUGCCCGUGGGGCCGGGAGCGAGUAAAGUCUGGGCCAGGCUGUGUGUGUGUAUCUUUGCUUUGAGGACUGGUGUUCUCUUUGGGGAUCCUGAUCCUGUCACCCCUGCCCUUGCUGCCCCUGAGACCUCGGAUGAGCCGUGGGCAUUGACUCUGGCUGUGCCCGUCCCCCGGUGAGCUGCAGAGAGCGAGGUUCAAUUCUGUGUUUUGUGUUUUUUUUUCUUUUCUUUUUUUGAGACGGAGUCUUGCUCAGUCACCCAGGCUGGAGUGCAGUGGCACGAUCUGGACUCACUACAACCUCCACCUCCAGAGUUCAAGUGAUUGUCCUGUCUCAGCCUCCUGAGUAGCUGGGAUUACAGGCACCCCGCUAUCAUGUAUGGCUAAUUGUAUUUUAGUAGAGAAGGGGUUUCACCAUGUUGGCCAGGCUGGGCUUGAACUCCUGACCUCAGGUGACCCACCUGCCUCAACCU